AGCUCUCUGCUCGCCGCCGCCGCUGUCGCCGCCACCUCCUCUGAUCUACGAAAGUCAUGUUACCCAACACCGGGAGGCUGGCAGGAUGUACAGUUUUUAUCACAGGUGCAAGCCGUGGCAUUGGCAAAGCUAUUGCAUUGAAAGCAGCAAAGGAUGGAGCAAAUAUUGUUAUUGCUGCAAAGACCGCCCAGCCACAUCCAAAACUUCUAGGCACAAUCUAUACUGCUGCUGAAGAAAUUGAAGCAGUUGGAGGAAAGGCCUUGCCAUGUAUUGUUGAUGUGAGAGAUGAACAGCAGAUCAGUGCUGCAGUGGAGAAAGCCAUCAAGAAAUUUGGAGGAAUUGAUAUUCUGGUAAAUAAUGCCAGUGCCAUUAGUUUGACCAAUACAUUGGACACACCUACCAAGAGAUUGGAUCUGAUGAUGAACGUGAACACCAGAGGCACCUACCUUGCAUCUAAAGCAUGUAUUCCUUAUUUGAAAAAGAGCAAAGUUGCUCAUAUCCUCAAUAUCAGUCCACCACUGAACCUAAAUCCAGUUUGGUUCAAACAGCACUGUGCUUAUACCAUUGCUAAGUAUGGUAUGUCUAUGUAUGUGCUUGGAAUGGCAGAAGAAUUUAAAGGUGAAAUUGCAGUCAAUGCAUUAUGGCCUAAAACAGCCAUACACACUGCUGCUAUGGAUAUGCUGGGAGGACCUGGUAUCGAAAGCCAGUGUAGAAAAGUUGAUAUCAUUGCAGAUGCAGCAUAUUCCAUUUUCCAAAAGCCAAAAAGUUUUACUGGCAACUUUGUCAUUGAUGAAAAUAUCUUAAAAGAAGAAGGAAUAGAAAAUUUUGACGUUUAUGCAAUUAAACCAGGUCAUCCUUUGCAACCAGAUUUCUUCUUAGAUGAAUACCCAGAAGCAGUUAGCAAGAAAGUGGAAUCAACUGGUGCUGUUCCAGAAUUCAAAGAAGAGAAACUGCAGCUGCAACCAAAACCACGUUCUGGAGCUGUGGAAGAAACAUUUAGAAUUGUUAAGGACUCUCUCAGUGAUGAUGUUGUUAAAGCCACUCAAGCAAUCUAUCUGUUUGAACUCUCCGGUGAAGAUGGUGGCACGUGGUUUCUUGAUCUGAAAAGCAAGGGUGGGAAUGUCGGAUAUGGAGAGCCUUCUGAUCAGGCAGAUGUGGUGAUGAGUAUGACUACUGAUGACUUUGUAAAAAUGUUUUCAGGGAAACUAAAACCAACAAUGGCAUUCAUGUCAGGGAAAUUGAAGAUUAAAGGUAACAUGGCCCUAGCAAUCAAAUUGGAGAAGCUAAUGAAUCAGAUGAAUGCCAGACUGUGAAGGAAAAUAUAAAAAAAAAGUCGACUGCUAUGCUCAAAAAGUAAAAAAAGCUCAACAGUUAAAAUCUAAUGUUUGUUUUCUUUCCUGUUAUAUUAUAAGGAUAUGCACGUUUGUUCUGGAAAAGAUAGAAUUUGUCUCUAAAAGACUUGAAAUUGUAAUUAAAAUGGCAAGCUAAUCAAACAUAAGCUUCAUUAAGUGGGAUUCUAAGACAGUCUGUGUUUUUAUAUUUCAAGGGUUUAACCCUUUGAGCCUUACAUCUCAUUCACUGUCUUUCUCCAAGAAAAGUAUUUUGGGCGGACAGUCAGAUCAAGCAGUAAAAUUAGCUCUUUCAAAUCUUCUUGUCAUGUAAAAUGAAGCUAGUCUGUUUUAAAAUUUUUAGUUUUGGAUUGUAUACUAAUGAAAAUCUUAAUGAUGUUUUUGAUUUUUAUAUACUUAUUUUAAAGAAAAUCUUAUAUAGUACAUUUUACAAAAAUUAUAAAAAAUGAAUUAGUACUGGCGAGGACUAAAUGAAACAAUAAUUUUUCAUUUUGAUAACUAGCUUUCCAGGUGGACUUAGCCAUAGGAAAAUAUUACUAAUGUAAUUUAACAAAUUGCUGCAUGUAUUCCAUUUAAAAAUAUGUUUAAAUUGUCCUAAAACAAAAUAAUUUUCUCCCUAGGAGUAUGCAUUUGGCUACAGUGUUUUGAAACAGAAACCUUAGAAUAGGUCAUUGGUAUGGGCUGAACUGUGUAUCCCCCAAUUCAUUUGUUGAGGUCCUAACUCCCAUUUCUUUUGAAUGUGACUGUUCGGAGAUGAGGCCUUUAAAGAGGUGACUUAAGUUCAAAGGAGGCUGUUAGUCUAAUCCAACAUGGUGUCCUUUGGACAUAAGAGAUACCAGCAAUGUGUGCACAGAACAAAGACCAGGAGAGGACACAGUGAGAAGGCAGUUAUCUGCAAGCAAAGAGAGAGGCUUCAGAAGAAACAAAAUCACCAGCACCUUGAUCUUUGACUUCUAAUCUCCAGAAUAGUGAGAAAUAAAUUUCUGUUGUUAAGCCGUCCACUGUGGGAGGCCGACGCAGGAGGAUUGCUUGAGGCCAGGAGUUCAAGGCCAGCCUGGACAACAUAGUAAGACCCUAUCUCUACCCCCCUAAUAAAUUAAUUUAAAAAGCCCCCCAAUCUGUGGUAUUUUAUUAUGGCAGCCCUAGCAAGCUAAUACAGUGGUUUGAGAGGCUGGGAGGGUUGAGGGGAAGAUAAACUUUUAAAAAGCUCUUAUCUUUCAUUUCAAUCAGUUAAAAAUACUUGCUCAGUGUAACAAUUUUGCUUCUCAGCUUCCACUCUAAUAUUGUUGUGCCAUUAAGCAAUUUAGCUAAUCCUGACAUUUCUUAGAUUCAUAAUGUUAGGAGCAUUUAAUCUGUAUUUUACAAGUUAGGAAGCAGAGGAUCAGAGAUGGGAAAGGACUAGCCCAAGGCCAACAUUAACAAGCCCUCUAACAAAAACUUUACAAUACAUUUAUGUUGAAUGGAACUCCAAGAUCUCACCUCUCCAUCCAGGAAUGGAGUCCAUGUAAUCAAAGUGAACUUAAAAAUAGGACAGUUUCAACAAGUCAGGAGAUUCACAGCAACUGAUCAAAGGGAGUCCAGUCAACGUGAGCAAGCGUGAUUAUGAUGAGGAAGCCCCCUCUGCUUUAAUCCACACAAGGAACGUAACCUGAAGUAACCUGAUGUUAACCAAUCUGCUGUGUCUACUAUGCUGUUUCCUUGUUCCUGCUAGUGCUGCUUUACAAAUGCAGACCAUUCUAUCAUACCUGGCGGGGCUUCUGUUUUAUUUUGUAGGCUGGAUGCUACCCAGUUCAUGAAUCGCUAAUAAAAGCCAAUUAGAUCUUUA